ACAACGAGCUCGGGCCUCACCCGGAUGGCGGCUGCGACGCGCGGCUGCCGGCCCUGGGGCUCGCUCCUCGGGCUGCUCGGGCUGGUCUCGGCCGCGGCCGCCGCCUGGGACCUGGCUUCCCUGCGCUGCACCUUGGGCGCCUUUUGCGAAUGCGACUUCCGGCCCGACUUGCCGGGUCUGGAGUGUGACCUGGCUCAGCACCUGGCCGGCCAGCAUCUGGCCAAGGCGCUGGUGGUGAAGGCGCUGAAGGCCUUUGUGCGGGACCCAGCCCCCACCAAGCCGCUGGUCCUCUCCCUGCACGGCUGGACCGGCACCGGCAAAUCCUAUGUCAGCUCCCUGCUGGCGCACUACCUCUUCCAGGGCGGCCUCCGCAGCCCCCGCGUGCACCACUUUUCUCCCGUCCUCCACUUCCCCCACCCCAGCCACAUCGAGCGCUACAAGAAGGAUCUGAAGAGCUGGGUCCAAGGGAACCUCACUGCCUGUGGCCGCUCCCUCUUCCUCUUCGAUGAGAUGGACAAGAUGCCCCCAGGCCUGAUGGAAGUCCUGCGGCCUUUCCUGGGCUCCUCCUGGGUGGUAUACGGGACCAAUUACCGCAAAGCCAUCUUCAUCUUCAUCAGGUGGGGCCCGGCUUUGCAGUGGGCACAGUGGGGGGGCCACUUCUCAGAGGUUCAGCUCUACAGCCUUAGCCUGUGCUCCCAGCAGAAUCCAGUUCCCCAUGGGCUUAGCUGGGCUUUCCCAGUGCCCUCCGCCACUCUCAGAGAUGACAUUGUCAUUCCGCCUGGUUGAUUUCCCUUUGGACAUUCUCAGCAAAUUCUGGGCUCAGUCUUUUUGAUCGCCACUUCUUUGUGGAAGCCCUGCCAGGUCAAGAAGUUUUCCCUCUUUUGUGGUGAGGAGGACACAGGCCUGGGAAAAAUAGGAACAGAGUUCUUGUCCUUUAGUCCCAGCUCUCAGAAUCCUCGCUGUGUUUCCUCAGGCAGCAUGGCUCCGCCUCUCUGAGCCUCUGUCUCUGCUUCUGAACAGCGGGGCCAAUAAUGAUGCCCCGAUGCCUUCCUGGAAGUUCAGUGAGGGAAAGUCAGUUGAGGGACACAAAAGUGUUUUGUAAACUAUAAAGUACGUGGCAUGUGUAGGUGAAUUACAGGGGCCAUGGAUGUGGACACCAUGGAGGGGGAAGUGGAGCGUUUUCAGUGGAGUUGGCUCCUCCCCGCACUGAGCCAUGUUCCUAUGUCAGGUGGCAGCGGGGAAGCGAGGGUCCAAUCCUGCCCUGCGCUAGUCCUCAUCUGAGUCUCAGCCUGGGUCCCCCAUGGUUUUAGCAACACGGGUGGCAAGCAGAUCAACCAGGUGGCAUUGGAGGCGUGGCGCAGCCGGCGGGACCGCGAGGAGAUCCUCCUGCAGGAGCUGGAGCCGGUCAUCUCCCGCGCGGUGCUGGACAACCCGCACCGUGAGUCUGGCUCAGCAGCCCCCUCCCGGGCAGCUUCACCCCACACCCAGGGGCCAGGCUCUCCCGGGGUCUCAUGCUUUGCCCACUGACCCGGCAGUUCUGAGCCUGGCUUUGGCACUCCCAGCUUUGUGACUUUGGGUGAGCCUUACAGCCCCUGAGUCCUACACCCAGAAGGCGGCUGAGGGAACUGAGGCCAGCAUUUUUCCUCCUGCCCCUGGGGGUUUGGGGCCGGCUUCUCCCCUCUUGUGAAGCACAAAGUCCCCUCCCCACCUACCCUUCCUGCAGAUGGCUUCUCAAACUCGGGCAUCAUGGAAGAGCGCCUCCUAGACGCAGUGGUGCCCUUCCUCCCGCUCCAGCGGCACCACGUCCGGCACUGCGUGCUCAACGAGCUGGCCCAGCUGGGCCUGGAGCCAAGGGAUGAGGUUGUCCAGGCUGUGCUGGACAGCACCACCUUCUUCCCUGAAGACGAGCAGCUCUUCUCCUCCAACGGCUGCAAGACCGUGGCCUCCCGAAUCGCCUUCUUCCUCUGACUCUCUGAGUGGUGUCCUCGGCCCCCCUGAUGGCCAGGCCAUGCAGGAAAGGCCAGGGGCCUCUGUCACAGGAACCCAGAGCACCAAGUGAGAUGAACGGAGUGUCGGCUAGGCCACGGGACAGAUGGCCAGGAAGGGCCCUGGCCUCUAAACUGGCUCGAGAGCAUCUUGGCCCCGGCCACCUUCCCCAGGGAAACCCCUGGUCACCCCAGAACCUCACUGAGCCUUGACCUCCCCCUGCAGCCUGAGCCUUCUUACUGUGAAUUAUAACUCAGGGACUGUGGCUCGUGGCGGUGCUCCCUCCUCAGUCUGCCACCCUUGCCCCUUGCCUCCUUGGUCGGGCACCAUACCUCCUCCCCUCCACCCCACACCCUGUGUCCAUAUCAAGCCAGGUGGAGCCUUCUCAGUUUCCAGAAAUGGAGGGACUCAAGCUGCCACUUGGGCCUGGUUUUAGAUGUUUUUAAUUUUGUAAAAGAAAACAAGUAUAAUAAACUCAGCUGUGGGACCAGA